AGGGAGAGGCAGAGAGGCAGGCAGCCUGCUGGGCUCUUCCUGCUGUUGAAAACUUACCCGGCCCUUACAGAGGAAAUCUUCCUCCUCUCUUCUGCCCUGAAUGUUUUCCCAAACAUGAAGGUGAUAAGCUUAUUCAUUUUGGUGGGAUUUAUAGGAGAGUUCCAAAGUUUUUCAAGUGCCUCCUCUCCAGUCAACUGCCAGUGGGACUUCUAUGCCCCUUGGUCAGAAUGCAAUGGCUGUACCAAGACUCAGACUCGCAGGCGGUCAGUUGCUGUGUAUGGGCAGUAUGGAGGCCAGCCUUGUGUUGGAAAUGCUUUUGAAACACAGUCCUGUGAACCUACAAGAGGAUGUCCAACAGAGGAGGGAUGUGGAGAGCGUUUCAGGUGCUUUUCAGGUCAGUGCAUCAGCAAAUCAUUGGUUUGCAAUGGGGAUUCUGACUGUGAUGAAGACAGUGCUGAUGAAGACAGAUGUGAGGACUCAGAAAGGAGACCUUCCUGUGAUAUCGAUAAACCUCCUCCUAACAUAGAACUUACUGGAAAUGGUUACAAUGAACUCACUGGCCAGUUUAGGAACAGAGUCAUCAAUACCAAAAGUUUUGGUGGUCAAUGUAGAAAGGUGUUUAGUGGGGAUGGAAAAGAUUUCUACAGGCUGAGUGGAAAUGUCCUGUCCUAUACAUUCCAGGUGAAAAUAAAUAAUGAUUUUAAUUAUGAAUUUUACAAUAGUACUUGGUCUUAUGUAAAACAUACGUCGACAGAACACACAUCAUCUAGUCGGAAGCGCUCCUUUUUUAGAUCUUCAUCAUCUUCUUCACGCAGUUAUACUUCACAUACCAAUGAAAUCCAUAAAGGAAAGAGUUACCAACUGCUGGUUGUUGAGAACACUGUUGAAGUGGCUCAGUUCAUUAAUAACAAUCCAGAAUUUUUACAACUUGCUGAGCCAUUCUGGAAGGAGCUUUCCCACCUCCCCUCUCUGUAUGACUACAGUGCCUACCGAAGAUUAAUCGACCAGUACGGGACACAUUAUCUGCAAUCUGGGUCGUUAGGAGGAGAAUACAGAGUUCUAUUUUAUGUGGACUCAGAAAAAUUAAAACAAAAUGAUUUUAAUUCAGUCGAAGAAAAGAAAUGUAAAUCCUCAGGUUGGCAUUUUGUCGUUAAAUUUUCAAGUCAUGGAUGCAAGGAACUGGAAAACGCUUUAAAAGCUGCUUCAGGAACCCAGAACAAUGUAUUGCGAGGAGAACCGUUCAUCAGAGGGGGAGGUGCAGGCUUCAUAUCUGGCCUUAGUUACCUAGAGCUGGACAAUCCUGCUGGAAACAAAAGGCGAUAUUCUGCCUGGGCAGAAUCUGUGACUAAUCUUCCUCAAGUCAUAAAACAAAAGCUGACACCUUUAUAUGAGCUGGUAAAGGAAGUACCUUGUGCCUCUGUGAAAAAACUAUACCUGAAAUGGGCUCUUGAAGAGUAUCUGGAUGAAUUUGACCCCUGUCAUUGCCGGCCUUGUCAAAAUGGUGGUUUGGCUACUGUUGAGGGGACCCAUUGUCUGUGCCAUUGCAAACCGUACACAUUUGGUGCGGCGUGUGAGCAAGGAGUCCUCGUAGGGAAUCAAGCAGGAGGGGUUGAUGGAGGUUGGAGUUGCUGGUCCUCUUGGAGCCCCUGUGUCCAAGGGAAGAAAACAAGAAGCCGUGAAUGCAAUAACCCACCUCCCAGUGGGGGUGGGAGAUCCUGCGUUGGAGAAACGACAGAAAGCACACAAUGCGAAGAUGAGGAGCUGGAGCACUUGAGGUUGCUUGAACCACAUUGCUUUCCUUUGUCUUUGGUUCCAACAGAAUUCUGUCCAUCACCUCCUGCCUUGAAAGAUGGAUUUGUUCAAGAUGAAGGUACAAUGUUUCCUGUGGGGAAAAAUGUAGUGUACACUUGCAAUGAAGGAUACUCUCUUAUUGGAAACCCAGUGGCCAGAUGUGGAGAAGAUUUACGGUGGCUUGUUGGGGAAAUGCAUUGUCAGAAAAUUGCCUGUGUUCUACCUGUACUGAUGGAUGGCAUACAGAGUCACCCCCAAAAACCUUUCUACACAGUUGGUGAGAAGGUGACUGUUUCCUGUUCAGGUGGCAUGUCCUUAGAAGGUCCUUCAGCAUUUCUCUGUGGCUCCAGCCUUAAGUGGAGUCCUGAGAUGAAGAAUGCCCGCUGUGUACAAAAAGAAAAUCCGUUAACACAGGCAGUGCCUAAAUGUCAGCGCUGGGAGAAACUGCAGAAUUCAAGAUGUGUUUGUAAAAUGCCCUACGAAUGUGGACCUUCCUUGGAUGUAUGUGCUCAAGAUGAGAGAAGCAAAAGGAUACUGCCUCUGACAGUUUGCAAGAUGCAUGUUCUCCACUGUCAGGGUAGAAAUUACACCCUUACUGGUAGGGACAGCUGUACUCUGCCUGCCUCAGCUGAGAAAGCUUGUGGUGCCUGCCCACUGUGGGGAAAAUGUGAUGCUGAGAGCAGCAAAUGUGUCUGCCGAGAAGCAUCGGAGUGCGAGGAAGAAGGGUUUAGCAUUUGUGUGGAAGUGAACGGCAAGGAGCAGACGAUGUCUGAGUGUGAGGCGGGCGCUCUGAGAUGCAGAGGGCAGAGCAUCUCUGUCACCAGCAUAAGGCCUUGUGCUGCGGAAACCCAGUAGGCUCCUGGAGGCCCUGGUCAGCUUGCUUGGAAUCCAGCAGGCAGCUGGGGCUGAGUGAAAACAUCUGCACAACUGGGCACUGGACAGCUUUUCCUUCUUCUCCAGUGUCUACCUUCCUCCUCAACUCCCAGCCAUCUGUAUAAACACAAUCCUUUGUUCUCCCAAAUCUGAAUCGAAUUACUCUUUUGCCUCCUUUUUAAUGUCAGUAAGGAUAUGAGCCUUUGCACAGGCUGGCUGCGUGUUCUUGAAAUAGGUGUUACCUUCUCUGGGCCUUGGUUUUUUAAAAUCUGUAAAAUUAGAGGAUUGCACUAGAGAAACUUGAAUGCUCCAUUCAGGCCUAUCAUUUUAUUAAGUAUGAUUGACACAGCCCAUGGGCCAGAACACACUCUACAAAAUGACUAGGAUAACAGAAAGAACGUGAUCUCCUGAUUAGAGAGGGUGGUUUUCCUCAAUGGAACCAAAUAUAAAGAGGACUUGAACAAAAAUGACAGAUACAAACUAUUUCUAUCCUGAGUAGUAAUCUCACACUUCAUCCUAUAGAGUCAACCACCACAGAUAGGAAUUCCUUAUUCUUUUUUUAAUUUUUUUAAGACAGAGUCUCACUUUGUUGCCCAGGCUGGAGCGCAGUGGGGUGAUCUCAUCUCCCUGCAACCUCCGCCUCCUGGGUUCAAGCGAUUCUUGUGCCUCAGCUUCCCAAGCAGCUGGGAUUACAGGUGCCCGCCACCACGCCCAGCUAAUUUUUGCAUUUUUAGUAGAGAUGGGGUUUCACCAUGUUGGCCACGCUCGUCUCCAACUCCUGACCUCAGGUAAUCCGCCUGCCUUGGCCUCCCAAAGUGCUGGGAUUACAGACAUGAACCACCACGCCUGGCUGGAAUACUUACUCUUGUCGGGAGAUUGAACCACUAAAAUGUUAGAGCAGAAUUCAUUAUGCUGUGGUCACAGGGGUGUCUUGUCUGAGAACAAAUACAAUUCAGUCUUCUCUUUGGGGUUUUAGUAUGUGUCAAACAUAGGACUGGAAGUUUGCCCCUGUUCUUUUUUCUUUUGAAAGAACAUCAGUUCAUGCCUGAGGCAUGAGUGACUGUGCAUUUGAGAAUAGUUUUCCCUAUUCUGUGGAUACAGUCCCAGAGUUUUCAGGGAGUACACAGGUAGAUUAGUUUGAAGCAUUGACCUUUUAUUUAUUCCUUAUUUCUCUUUCAUCAAAACAAAACAGCAGCUGUGGGAGGAGAAAUGAGAGGGCUUAAAUGAAAUUUAAAAUAAGCUAUAUUAUACAAAUACUAUCUCUGUAUUGUUCUGACCCUGGUAAAUAUAUUUCAAAACUUCAGAUGACAAGGAUUAGAACACUCAUUAAAGAUGCUAUUCUUCAGAAUUGUUUCAUUUGUAUGAUGUUUCAUUUUAGAGAAGAUUUUCAUGAUGAAUGGUUAAUGUGUUCUUGCCUGAAGUUUUAUGUCUGAUCCAGAUCUAGCUUUUUGUAUCAAAGUGUGCCCUAAGGGAAGAUGCAGAUAUAAUAUGUUGAAGUUACAAGGAGGCAGGUUUCAAUUGGUUAAAAACAAUGACAUUCAGACAUUGCAACUGCAUUUGUUAGCGGUUAUUACAGAGUUAAUUUCUACCCUGGAUGGGAGGACACAUUUGAACAUGCUAGGCCUGGAUGCAGACCCUGAGACAAAAGGUUGAACAAGUAAUUCAUUUGGAAGGAAAUACCUCAGUAUCCUUCCAAUAAUUUCUCCUCUUAGCUUAAGCUAGUAUGGAGUUAGAUUCCUACCGCUUAUGUAUCACCAUGCCCCCUUCCUAAAUAAUACAGAGGAUAUGGUCAGCAUUAUCACAUAUCAUCAGAGAUUGAGGUUUGAAAGAAAGGAAAUGAGUAGAUGUAACUAAGAGGUUUGAGAAAGGAAUUUCAGCAGAGUUAUUGAAGGAGAAGUCAAGGAGAGGAGAAGGAGAGGAGCAGUGAAUGUUGUCGUGAAGAGGUGUUGUCUUGAAAUACUGUAUUUUUUUCCUCCUUUUCUUUUCUGAACAUUCUUGUGCUGACCUUUCCUCUAGUCCAACAGAGGCAUUCACAAUUGCCUGUGGAGAAUUAGGAUUGUCGCAGCAGGUCAGCAAGGAGAAAGUCAUUUUUAAGAUUAAAUUUUUAAAAAUGUUUUGAAACUUCCAAAAUAAGUUCUUGAACACCUAUGGAGAGGCUUUGAGGAAAGUUAAGGGAAUGAUUUUAUACCACAAAAAUAAAUGGAAAAAGAAUAAAGACUGUGAGAAUUCCAUCUUCCUGCCCUUUCCUGUGCCUCAGAUCAGGUGAGGGUCAUCUGGGUUAGAAGGGGAUAGAGCCUUGGAGGAGGCAGAGGGCAGAAAGCAUUGCUGAGAUUAGAGUCAUUUGGCCCUCAGAAGGAACAGACAAAGAGAAGGAAAUUGGCUGGUGCAUUAAUCAUCACUAGCUUCAGGGAGCUAUGUGGAGGCCAAGGCACAUCCUACAGAUCAUCGCUUACCACUCAUGAGGACGCUACAAGUUACCUGGGCAGAGAAGGUGCCUGAGAAUAUUUCCUAAUCGUUUUGAGAAGUGCCUUCCUGUGACAUCUUAUGUAUUUCCUAAUUGAUCAAAAGUAGUGCUGCUUCUCUAAGCCCUGAGAUUUAAUGAGCCCCAUUCAAACUGUUAUUAAUGUAACCUUCUUUCCCAGUGCAGGAUGACUUGUAAUCACCUUGAAAGAGAAGGAGGGUUCUUCGUAUUCAGGUAGGGUAUGGUAGGGAUGUGGAGUGCCAAGCAGGAAAUCUGACAAGUGACCCCCGGAACUUUGGAUUACCUAGCAACUAGCCAGGUAACUGGCUAAUCUGAUUGAGGGUUGCCCUCUUUGCUGGGCAGAUCAUGGCUAAUCUCAGCUUCACAUGAGUCUUGUGAACCAUCUAGUUGUUUUGUAACUGCUAAGAGCUGCAAGUGCUGAGCAGCUGGUUUAUACAGCAUUCCCUGAAACAGCCUAGUAUGUGUCCAUUUAUGUGCCCGGCUUAUUAUGUGUCCACUUAUGUGUCCAAUUAGUAAUCACUUUUUCUUUCGGUCAAGGUAUGUGUAUUAAUCAAUAUUUUUUGAACCCGU